ACUGUUGCCUGGCGACGGGUCCCUGCGUCAUGGCGGAGAAGGGGACCUCUGUGGACGUGCAUCGCCGUUGGACUCUCGCCUGUCUUCUCUGAAGGAUCCAUGGGAUAGUCCCGCGAUCCUAGAAGUGUGCUGGGGCGACCCAGCCUGAAGAAACCUCAAGCGGAGCCCAAGGGAUACAGCGCAAAAUUCCUAAGGAUCCGCAGGAUGCUUCAGGCCUGCCUAGACGGUGUGGGUGUGAGUCUCCUUGAAACUUGCCCCCCUGUGAUUUCUAGGCUUGAAAUCGCCCUUAGACAGCCUCUGAGACACUUUCUCAACCUCACCUGCCCCGGUGGGAUGCCAACUCCAGGUGUCAGACCUCUGCUCCACCUUGGACUAGCCUUUGUCGUGGUUCCUGCCUUUCCCAGACGACCGUGCUGAGAAGCAGGAGCCCCUGUGAGGCCCAGGAUGAAGGAAGACAGUGAGCUUAAGGACACAGGAAUCUUCCGCUAGCACCAUCAUCCAGAAUUUUAACUAAAAUUCCAUCUCAAAGAGACCCCUCAAAAACUCACAAGACUGUAUCUCCAGCCCAAUGGGACCCGAUUCCUACACACAGCCUUUUUCGGGAAUGGAAUCAGAAACGCAGUUUCCAUGGCCCAACUCACAGUCUCAAAGCCUGUCCUCCUCCAGCGGGACAGGGCCACGGAGACAAACUAAGGAAGCCCUACGGUGAGCAACGUUGGGGGCCCGCAGUACUUGUUGCAGGCAGCCUAUUUCCUGAGACCAGGCAGGCUCUGCCUGCACCAUUUUCCUUGCUUAGGUAGGCUGAAAACCCUGACAGCCUGGUGACCGAAACUGCCUCAUGCAUGCACCAGUGGCGGGGCACCAGGAGCAAGUAGUGAGCGCGGGCUCGAGUCACAGUGAAUGCCUUCGUUGCAUCUCGACAAGUCUCUGACUCUUGGCAAAGAGGGGGUCCUCUGUGACGUGCGUCGAAGUUGGACUUCCGGUUGUCUUCUCUGGGGAUCCAUGGGAUACUCCCACGAUCCAGGAUACAAUAGAGGCAGACCAUUCUGAGGAAAUGUCAAGUAGCACUUAGCACCUGCCCGCCCUCCACCUUCUCCACCACCCAGCAGGAGCGGGGCGGCCUGGAUCUGUUUUCUGCCCCUGACCAGGGGGCCGCGUCUUCGGCAAAGUCUUCGGGGUGAGAGGUCCGGCUCCUGGAGGACAGCGGGAUGGGAGAGUCCCGUUCACACCCAGCCCCGCAGAGCCGGAUAGAAACGCUGCCACUGCCGACUCCAUGCUGCCGGGAAGUGCACUGUGGAGGCCACUUUCUGGAAAGAAGAAACCGUCUGAACACAAAGUUGCUCAAGCCAUGUUCAUCUAUCUGCCAGGGAAACGGAGGCCCUGAGUGCCAGAGUCCAAGUCACCCUGCAAGAGAAAACUCUGGUGGAGCCCAGGGUGUCCAGCCCCUGUCCACCCAGCCGCCGUGGUCAAGGUUAAUAAGGGCAAGGGGCCAAGCAGAACCGCCUACAAGGAACCGAGUGUCCACAAAGCAGGAAGCGAAGAACGUUUCUCCUACCUAGAGCGCAGCCGUUUUGCGGAAGGCACAGUCCGGGCUCCGGGAGCCAAGCAGGGAUCCGGGCCUCGUUGCGGAGGGGACGCCCGGGCUGAGCUGAGCUCACUUGCUGGCGGCGGCAGCCCCUGCAGUCAUGGGGUCACCGGCUUGUGGAGAGGGGCUGGCGCUGUUCCUUGGCCCCGCUCCCCGCCCGCAAAGGGCCGGGAGGUCGGGCUCCCGGCAGUGUCCAGGCUCUCGCCCGCCGGUGCCUGAGCCGUACCCACCGCGUCCCCUCCGCCCCAACAGCUGGUGCUGAGGGUCCGGCCCGGGGUCAUCUGGCAGGGCCGUGCGGCUCCUGCGGGUGACCAGGAGCGCGGAGCCCCUUCCCACUCGGGCUCGGGUGGCCUCACCUUUCCUGGGGCUGCGUCCCCGCGGGACGCCAGGUUCCCGGUUUCUUCUAGGUCGCCCUGGUUCCUGGCAGCUCCUGGUGCCACGCGGUCCUCUACGGUCUCCUCUGACCUGAGAGGGACAGUGAGAUGGGGCUGGCGGGGAUGGGGGUCCCCGCGCUGUUGGAAAGCAGCGGGGCUGCUGCUGACCGGAGCCGCCUGGGUCUGUUCUGGAACCGUCGCCCUGGGGCCCCUCCGCCCCGCAAACGCUCGGGAUGCGGUUUGGGAGUGUAGCUGGACACCGAGCACCAUCCACGCUCAGCCCCACGGGGCUCCAGGAGUCCCGAGCCCAAGCCCCUGCACUUGCAUUUUAUUUAAAAAACCUGAGGGUUAAAUUCGGGCAAGUCAGUUGCCUCAGUGUUUGUCGCCUGCUGCCUCUAUGUCGGCUUCUUUUGCUGGCAGUCAGAGACCAAGCCCCCACGCCCUCCAGGACCCUCUAUCUGGUGAGGCCACCUCUGCAAUCAUGAGCAGCACUGAGGUGCUUCCGACCAGGGGUCACUGCCCCAGCCGGUGAGAGGCCCUGCAGUGGGGACUGGAGAUGUGCGACGCAGCCUCCCAGAGCCCGCAUCCUCUUGCCCAAGGAGGCUGCACACCCUCACUCAGGGCUGUGAGGGGGAAUGAGGGCAGCUCACAGGCUAAGGGGCCGCUGAAGACAGGUUUUGUGGACAGGUGAUUUAGGAGCCUGGAGGAAGCAGGUUAGGGGUGUGUGUGUGUGUGUGUGUGUGUGUGUGUGUGAGAGAGAGAGAGAGGGAAUUCUCCCAUGCCAGGACAUCUGCGUGUCUCAGUAGAGUAGGAGUGAACAGCAGCAUCCCUGCAGAGGAGCAGCAUGUGGACAGAGUCACAGGCUGGCUGGAUCACAACAAAUCCUUGUGGGUCAAGGAGAGCAGGUUCCGUGAUCAGCUGCGGUCUGGGUUUUGUGUUUGCCUUUUCCUGCUGUUCCAAUAAGCCAGGGCACUGGGGCCAGAUUGCCCUCAGCCAUGGCCAAGGGUUCCCUGACAAGCUGGGGAGGACGAACUCCCUUCCCAACACAGGGACAUAGAAGAUCAGAGCAGCCUGCCCAGUGGGGAUCUGAGCUCAGAGAGUGGAAGCCACUGUCUCAGAGUCACAGAGCAGGUCAGUGGCAGGUCCCAUGUCCCUGACCCCCAAGCUCUAUUUCUCUGAGGAAAUAUUCCAUCCAAGAGCAUGAGAGUCCUCUGAGCAUGGACUCCCUGGCAGGUGAGGUCAUUUUACCUGUUAUCUGUUUUCAUCCUCAUUGUGUGUGUGGUUUGUAUCAGUGUCCCCAUUGUAAGGCAGAAAACAGGCUCAGUGAUGGGGCAAAGGCUGGUGCAAGGCUACAGAGCUCAGAAGUGGCUGAGGUGAGACAAGAACCAGCAGGCUUCCUUCACCGUUGCUCUGCUCCAUCUGGAGGUUGGACAAUUUGCCUGUGUGCCAACAGCCACAAGCCUUUGUUGGCUCAGGGUAGAUAUGAAAACCUGGAAACCAUGAAGCUUUCAGCCCCACUCAUUUCUGCAGGGGCAGAUGGCUGUGCUUGGCCUGGGCUCCCCAUUGCUCAAAAUAGAGCCUCCUCUUUCUGCCAGUGGUCCCAGAAAUGAGUCACAGGUGGGUGAGGUUGCAGCCAGGCCUGGGCAGGAUGAUGUCUUCUGGGCUAGGCUGAAAACUCAAGCCUUGCAGCUGGACAAGUUAUGACUUUGGUUCUGCCUCAGUCACUCCGAGGCUGGACAACUCUGGCCAUAUCUCUCUGUAAGCUGUGGUUUCCUUAUCUUUAAAAUGGAGACAAUGGCACCUCUCUCCCAGAGUAGCCACUGGGGCUUAAUAAAGCCUCAGCAUGAGAAGAUGGUGUAUUUGUAUUUGUGAGUUUUCCUUGGUCUAUGGUGACCUUCCUGUGGGUAAGAACCAAGUAUCACUUGGCUCAGGACCCAGACAGGCACAGCACAGCCAGAACCAGAGGGGCCUAGGCCUGGGUAUGAUUGGAAUCCAGGCAUCUGGCCCAGUUUUUCUGGCUCUGUCUCCUUCCCCAUCUUUUCCAAACUGGUCCAAGGAUCAGAUUUGCCAUGUCACCCAGACAUCGUUGUGGCCCUGUCUGAACAAGCAGCAUCAGAAUUUCUCUGGUGCCAGCUGGAUGACUCAGAGAGAAAAACUGGUCACCAAUUUCUGCUUCAAGUGGGUAGGGAAGAAAGCUACCACUUGCAGCUACUUAUUAUGUAUCACCAGCCAGGCACUUUUCCUACUUAGUGGUCACCUCAGCUAAGUCAUAAAGACACAGAAAAGAGUGCCUUGCCCCAGGUUCACAGCUGAUAAGUGGGGUGUGGGAGAGGAGGUGCUGAAAUCCACAUUUAUCUAAACCUUUCAGACCCAUGUGCAUUUCUCCAUUUUUACCACAUUGUCCCCUCCUUGGUGACAGCCUGGGCUGCUGCUCCUGCCUCUCACUGGCCUCUCUGCCUCCAAGCUGCCUGUGCCUUAGGAAGCUCCAUGUUGCACUUUCAAACCAGCAGCCCAAUCCAUCCCUCACCUACUUGUGCCUUUCAAUGACUCUCAUUGUCCUCAGAAAAUGACCCUGGCUCCUAGGUGUCCACACCUCUGUGGCCCUGAGCAGGCUGACAGAAAUAAAACUGCAUGCCUCCUUUCCUUCCAGUGAAAAGAAAUCACUGGAUAUUGCAACAAAAUUUAAACUUAUCAUUUGGGAGAAAUCAGAGUAUCCUCUUUCAUAGACAAAAAAAACAGUAUUCAACCCUAAAAGGAAAGAAAACAAUUCUCUUGAAUGCUGCCACACUUGGAAAAACAAUGGAAAAUAAACACUGGAACCAGCUAGACCUGCCAGAGUUGCUGAGGGAGGAUUAAAUGAGUUAUUAUGUAAUUUGCUUAGCAACAGUGCUUGGCUCAUAGUUAGUGCUCAGUAAUAUCAGCUAUUCUUUUUUUUAUUGUAAAUAGAAGAGAAGCUAGGAAUGAAUCCAUGACCUUGGAUGGGCAUCCUCUGUCUUCCCCAGGACAGGGGUUCAGUGUCAUUUUCCAGGAACCUAAUGAAGCAGCCUUGUUCUUCUGGGGUGAUACCCGAGAUUUGUUGCCUAAUGGUCAUAAAAAACUAGGAUGUGGACACACAAGAGUGAGGUUAAGAGCAGAAGUUUAAUAGGUGGAAGAAAGAGAAAAGCUCCCUGUGCUGCAGAGAGAGGGGUCCCAAAUGGGCUGCAGGAUCCACAGUGAAAUGCAUGGGAUUUUAUAGAUGCCUGAUGAGGGGGGCGGUGUUUGAUUUACACAGGGCACGAAAGAUUGGUUGGACCAGGUAUGUCAUUUGCAUGGAGCAUGAAAAAUUGGUUAGAGGUAUGUCAUUUGCAUGGAUUACGGAAAAUUUGCAUAGGUGGCAAAUUUGUGUCCACUCCCACCCUAAUCUUGUAUUAUGUAAGUGGGUCUUAAGUGGGUCUUCUUCCUGAGCUGCAUCAUAUUGCCCAUUCCUUUACUCUACAUGUAGUAACAACAACAACAACAAAAAUGGAGCCUCUGUGUUGGACAUGCCUGGCCCACAGGUAGCCCUUUUCUAUUGGCACAGCUGCCGGCAUUCACCCUUCCAAGCUUCCAGCUUGCUUAUCUAUGUUUGCAGCUCCAUUUUUCAGGCUGAUCUUUGUUAGUAAAGAAAAAAAAAAAUUUGUCUUCCUUUUGCUAAAGGGAAGCUCUGCCAAGUACUCUUUUAUGCUCACUGUCUGUCAAAUAUUUUUUUUCUACUUUCUGUAUCAUUAAGACUCAUCAUCACUCAGAGACAACCAAACACUGUGACAUUUUGAUAUAACCCUUUCCAAAAGUGUAUAUUUUUCACAGUUUUGAGCACGCAUUGCAUACCAUUUUUUCACUGAACACAAUCUAUCAUGAACAUCUUUCCAUAACUUAAAAGAAGCUGCAUGCCAGAACAGUCCAUCAUGUUCUGUUUUCUUUCAGAAAUCUUUAGAGAUGGAUCAUUUUCCUUACAAGAAUAGAUACCAGGUAAGAGAAGCAGCCUUUAAAGCAGCGAAUAGCAGCUCAUGCAUGCUAAUUAUUUGCUUACUUCUCUGGCUCCCCUAUUGAUGGCAUCUUGAGGGCCGGUAUGAACAUGUCAUGCAGUCUCCAAGCAACCCACAGUAGGCCCACCAUAAACAGAUGUUGUGGCCAGCAUGGGAGGUGCAAUGGUGAGUUGCUCUGUUUCCUCCCUCCCGUCCCCCUCCCCACCCCUCCCCUCCCCCUCCCCUCCCCCUCCCCUCCCUUCCCCUUCCCUUCCCUUCCUCUCUCACAAAACAGUCACAGAGAGAGGACAGCAGCGUACAUGGUGAGGUGCUGACGAUUCUGGUCCACUGGAUCCCACCAUCCCUAGGACAGUAAAUACCGUCCUAGUCACUACCCAGCAAGUUACCACCGCAUCAUUUCCUGCAUGUUCCAAAAUGAAUAAAGACGGAAUCUUGCUCUGUCGCCCAGACUGGAGUGCAGUGGCGCAAUCUCAGCUCACUUCAAGCUCUGCCUCCCAGUUUCACGCCAUUCUCCUGCCUCAGCCUCCCGAGUAGCUGGGACUACAGGCGCCCGCCACCACACCCAGCUAAUUUUUUGUAUUUUUAGUAGAGACGGGGUUUCACUGUGCUGGCCAGCAUGGUCUCGAUCUCCUGAGCUCGUGAUCCACCCGCCUCGGCCUCCCAAAGUGCUGGGAUUACAGGCAUGAGCCACCGUGCCCAGCCAAAAAGCUGAUGUGUUUUAAGCAAAAUAAGCAUACGCAUCAAUAGUAAAAUGCUUCUGGUAAAAUAAAGGUUCAUUUUGUUGAUUUCUUUUUUUUUUUUUUUUUCUGAGACGGAGUCUUGCUCUGUCGCCCAGUCUGGAGUGCAGUGGCACGGUCUCUGCUCACUGCAAGCUCUGCCUCCUGGGUUCACGCCAGUCUCCCGUCUCAGUCUCCCGUCUCAGCCUCCCGAGUAGCUGGGACUACAGGCGCCUGCCACCACGCCCGGCUAAUUUUUUGUAUUUUUUAGUAGAGACAGGGUUUCACCGUGUUAGCCAGGAUGGUCUCGAUCUCCUGACCUCGUAAUCCUCCCGCCUCGGCCUCCCAAAGUGCUGGUAUUACAGGCGUGAGCCACCGCACCCGGCCUCAUUUUGCUGAUUUCUCUUGAGCUCAGGCCAGAAAAACUGGGAAAAUCACAGGCUCUUCCACUUACUGGAUGUUUGACAAAAUAUUCUUCUUGGGCCAAAAACAUUGGCAUUACUGGGACCACUGACAUUUAGGGAUGUGGCCAUAGAAUUCUCUCUGGAGGAGUGGCAAUGCCUGGACACUUCACAGCAGAAUUUGUAUAGGAAUGUGAUGUUAGAUAACUACAGAAACCUGGUCUUCCUGGGUAUUGCUGUCUCUAAGCCAGACCUGAUCACUUGUCUGGAGCAAGGAAAAGAGCCCUGCAAUAUGAAGAGACAUGCGAUGGUAGCCAAACCCCCAGUUGUGUGUUCUCAUUUUGCCCAAGACCUUUGGCCAAAGCAGGGCUUAAAAGAUUCUUUUCAAAAAGUGAUACUGAGAAGAUAUGGAAAAUAUGGACAUGAGAAUUUACAAUUAAGAAAAGGCUGUAAAAGUGCGGAUGAGCAUAAGGUGCACAAAAGAGGUUAUAAUGGACUUAACCAAUGUUUGACAACUACCCAGAGCAAAAUAUUUCAAUGUGAUAAAUAUGUUAAAGUCCUUCAUAAAUUCUCAAAUUCAAAUAUACAUAAGAAAAGACAAACUGGAAAGAAACCUUUCAAAUGUAAAGAAUGUGGCAAAUCAUGUUGCAUACUUUCACAACUAACUCAGCAUAAGAAAACUGCUACUAGAGUGAAUUUCUACAAAUGUAAGACAUGUGGAAAAGCCUUUAACCAGUUCUCAAAUCUUACUAAACAUAAGAUAAUUCAUCCUGAAGUGAAUCCCUACAAAUGUGAAGAAUGUGGCAAAGCCUUUAACCAGUCCUUAACUCUUACUAAACAUAAAAAAAUUCAUACUGAAGAGAAACCUUACAAAUGUGAAGAUUGUGGCAAAGUCUUUAGUGUAUUUUCAGUCCUUACUAAACAUAAGAUAAUUCAUACAGGAACAAAACCCUACAAUUGUGAAGAAUGUGGCAAAGGCUUUAGUAUAUUCUCAACCCUUACUAAACAUAAGAUAAUUCAUACUGGAGAGAAACCCUACAAAUGCAAUGAAUGUGGUAAAGCCUUUAACUGGUCCUCAACUCUUACUAAACAUAAGAGAAUUCAUACUGGAGAGAAACCCUACAAAUGUGAAGAAUGUGGCAAAGCUUUUAACCAGUCCUCAACCCUUACUAGACAUAAGAUAGUUCAUACUGGAGAGAAACCCUACAAAUGUGAAGAAUGUGGUAAAGCCUUUAAACGGUCCACAACUCUUACUAAACAUAAGAGAAUUUAUACUAAAGAGAAACCAUACAAAUGUGAAGAAUGUGGAAAAGCCUUUAGUGUAUUCUCAACCCUUACUAAACAUAAGAUAAUUCAUACUGGAGCAAAACCUUACAAAUGUGAAGAAUGUGGCAGUGCCUUUAGGGCAUUCUCAACCCUUACUGAACAUAAGAGAGUUCAUACUGGAGAGAAACCUUACAAAUGCAAUGAAUGUGGUAAAGCCUUUAACUGGUCCUCAACUCUUACUAAACAUAAGAGAAUUCAUACUGGAGAGAAGCCCUACAAAUGUGAAGAAUGUGGCAAAGCUUUUAACCGGUCCUCAAACCUUACUCGACAUAAGAAAAUUCAUACUGGAGAGAAACCAUACAAACCUAAAAGAUGUGACAGUGCUUUUGACAACACCCCAAACUUUUCUAGACAUAAAAGAAAUCAUAUGGGUGAGAAAUCCUAGAAAUGUGAAGAAUGUGACAAAGCCUUUAAGCGGUUGUCACACUUGAUUGUAUAUAAGAUAAUUCAUACUGGAGAAAACUCCCAGAAGUGGAGUUUUCCUUAUUGCACAGGAAAGCAUUUAUACUUGAGAAAAAUUGUAUAAAGAAUGGAAAAGUCAUUAAUAUCUGCUCAUAUCUUAACAUCAGCGAGUUGGUAUUUAAUAAAAGCAUUAUCAAUGAAAUUACUGUCAAAAGAUCUUUCAGACAAUAUAAGCCUGCAAAGUGCAGCAGAGUAUUUAUUUUGAAGAGAAACAUUAAAAGUACAAAGAGGUUUGUAGUACCUUUGUUUGUAUCAUAGAUCUUAUUGUACACAUUUUGUACCAGAGAAAAACCCUGAAGCAGUUGUUCAAACUUUGUUCAAUACCAGGAAAUUUAUAUUGGAGAAAAACCCUAUGAGUGUAAUGAAUUUGGAAAAAUAUUUUUUUCAACAACAGCUUAGAAAACAUGGGAGGAAUUACACUAAAAUAUAUUUUUGCAAAUGCAGCAGUAAAUAUGAAAGAAAUGAUCCAAAGUUAGGUUUAUAUAAAUAUCAGAGAAUUCACAAUACAGAUAUCUAAGAUACUGACACUUCAGACAUUACACAAAAUCAGAGUGCUGAGUACAGAAAGUUAUCCAAAACAAAAGUUGGUAGAUAACUAAUAGUGAACAAGUUUUUGGCAGAGGUAUAUUUACAUUCAGAGUACACUUUUCUUUGGAAAAAAUUACAGGUUUUUUGAAAAGUGAAUAAUGUAAUUCAACUCUCAAAUUCAUGGUUUUUUUUUUUUUGGUUUUGGUUUUGGGUUUUUUGUUUGUUUGUUUGUUUGUUUUUGAGACGGAGUUUCACUCUUGUUGCCCAGGCUGGAGUGCAAUGGCGUGAUCUCAGCUCACCGCAACCUCUGCCUCCCAGAUUCAAGCAAUUCUCCUGCCUCAGCCUCCCUAGUAGCUGGGAUUACAGGCAUGUGCCACACCUGGCUAAUUUUUGUGGUUUUAGUAGAGACAGGGUUUCUCCAUGUUGGUCAGUCUGGUCUCAAACUCCCAACCUCAGGUGAUAUGCCCGCCUCGGCCUCCCAAAAUGUUGGGAUUACAGGCAUGAGCCACUGCACCCGGCGCAUGUUUUUUCUUCAUUCCUAUUGUAUUCACAUGUGAAAGCAUGUGAUCAACUUGCUGCAUCAAAGAUAUGAGAUUUUUUUUUUUAUUAGGUGGGCAUUAUUUAUGACCUUUUCUGUGGAAGAGUAAGAACAUUAAAAUGAAAGAUGCAUGAUGAAAAUCUAAGUAGAGAGGCUCUUGUGGUUAACUGAUAAUAUUGAGUGAUGCAUGAGGUAGGUGUUCAGAGUAAUAUUCUGCAUUAUAGUGAAAAAUUUUUAAUAUUAAAAUUCAAUUAUAUCAUUUUAUGAAUUGUGCUUUUCAUAAUGCAGUACAUUUCAAAAUUUUUAGAUUAUGUAUGAACUUAGAUUUUUAAACAUGUUUUAACAUGUUAAGACUUGUGCAUUCAGUGAAGCGUUAUUAUGCCACAAACUAACCUACCUCACCUUACUCAAUGGUGUAGGUAAAAGAUGAUAGCAAUAUAUUAUUUGGUUACAUAGUGGACUAACAUUUUUAGUAAUCUCUUUUGCCAGUGGCUUUAAACUGCAGAUAAGUUAAAUAUUCCCAUAGGUUUUACAUUUAUAUUUUUUCUUAUUUAAAUUUAUUGUUCUUAUUUUUCAUGGGUACAUAGUAUGUUUUUAUGCUGUAUAUGGCAUGUUUUGAUACAGGUAUAUAAUAUGUAAUAAUCACAUCAGGGUAAAUGAGGUAUCCCUUACUAGCAUUUAUCCUUUGUAUUUUAUUUUAAAAUGUACAACUAAAUUGUUAUGGACUACAGGGUUAUUUUUAUGGUCAUAAUAAAAAUUACAAAAGUAUGAAUAAAAUACAUACAUUUCUGAGUCCUGAA